AGAGAAAUCAAAGAUGGCGGUUGUAUCUGCUGUUCGCUGGCUGGGCCUCCGCAGCAGGCUUGGCCAGCCGCUGACGGGUCGGCGGGCGGGUUUGUGUGAACAGGCACGCAGCUGCAGAUUUUAUUCUGGUAGUGCAACCCUCUCAAAGGUUGAAGGAACUGAUGUAACAGGGAUUGAAGAAGUAGUAAUUCCAAAAAAGAAAACUUGGGAUAAAGUAGCCGUUCUUCAGGCACUUGCAUCCACAGUAAACAGGGAUACCACAGCUGUGCCUUAUGUGUUUCAAGAUGAUCCUUACCUUAUGCCAGCAUCAUCUUUGGAAUCUCGUUCAUUUUUACUGGCAAAGAAAUCCGGGGAGAAUGUGGCCAAGUUUAUUAUUAAUUCAUACCCCAAAUAUUUUCAGAAGGACAUAGCUGAACCUCAUAUACCGUGUUUAAUGCCUGAGUACUUUGAACCUCAGAUCAAAGACAUAAGUGAAGCCGCCCUGAAGGAACGAAUUGAGCUCAGAAAAGUCAAAGCCUCUGUGGACAUGUUUGAUCAGCUUUUGCAAGCAGGAACCACUGUGUCUCUUGAAACAACAAAUAGUCUCUUGGAUUUAUUGUGUUACUAUGGUGACCAGGAGCCCUCAACUGAUUACCAUUUUCAACAAACUGGACAGUCAGAAGCAUUGGAAGAGGAAAAUGAUGAGACAUCUAGGAGGAAAGCUGGUCAUCAGUUUGGAGUUACAUGGCGAGCAAAAAACAACGCUGAGAGAAUCUUUUCUCUAAUGCCAGAGAAAAAUGAACAUUCCUAUUGCACAAUGAUCCGAGGAAUGGUGAAGCACCGAGCUUAUGAGCAGGCAUUAAACUUGUACACUGAGUUACUAAACAACAGACUCCAUGCUGAUGUAUACACAUUUAAUGCAUUGAUUGAAGCAACAGUAUGUGCGAUAAAUGAGAAAUUUGAGGAAAAAUGGAGUAAAAUACUGGAGCUGCUAAGACACAUGGUUGCACAGAAGGUGAAACCAAAUCUUCAGACUUUUAAUACCAUUCUGAAAUGUCUCCGAAGAUUUCAUGUGUUUGCAAGAUCGCCAGCCUUACAGGUUUUACGUGAAAUGAAAGCCAUUGGAAUAGAACCCUCGCUUGCAACAUAUCACCAUAUUAUUCGCCUGUUUGAUCAACCUGGAGACCCUUUAAAGAGAUCAUCCUUCAUCAUUUAUGAUAUAAUGAAUGAAUUAAUGGGAAAGAGAUUUUCUCCAAAGGACCCGGAUGAUGAUAAGUUUUUUCAGUCAGCCAUGAGCAUAUGCUCAUCUCUCAGAGAUCUAGAACUUGCCUACCAAGUACAUGGCCUUUUAAAAACCGGAGACAACUGGAAAUUCAUUGGACCUGAUCAACAUCGUAAUUUCUAUUAUUCCAAGUUCUUCGAUUUGAUUUGUCUAAUGGAACAAAUUGAUGUUACCUUGAAGUGGUAUGAGGACCUGAUACCUUCAGCCUACUUUCCCCACUCCCAAACAAUGAUACAUCUUCUCCAAGCAUUGGAUGUGGCCAAUCGGCUAGAAGUGAUUCCUAAAAUUUGGAAAGAUAGUAAAGAAUAUGGUCAUACUUUCCGCAGUGACCUGAGAGAAGAGAUCCUGAUGCUCAUGGCAAGGGACAAGCACCCACCAGAGCUUCAGGUGGCAUUUGCUGACUGUGCUGCUGAUAUCAAAUCUGCGUAUGAAAGCCAACCCAUCAGACAGACUGCUCAGGAUUGGCCAGCCACCUCUCUCAACUGUAUAGCUAUCCUCUUUUUAAGGGCUGGGAGAACUCAGGAAGCCUGGAAAAUGUUGGGGCUUUUCAGGAAGCAUAAUAAGAUUCCUAGAAGUGAGUUGCUGAAUGAGCUUAUGGACAGUGCAAAAGUGUCUAACAGCCCUUCCCAGGCCAUUGAAGUAGUAGAGCUGGCAAGUGCCUUCAGCUUACCUAUUUGUGAGGGCCUCACCCAGAGAGUAAUGAGUGAUUUUGCAAUCAACCAGGAACAAAAGGAAGCCCUAAGUAAUCUAACUGCAUUGACCAGUGACAGUGAUACUGACAGCAGCAGUGACAGCGACAGUGACACCAGUGAAGGCAAAUGAAAGUGGAGAUUCAGGAGCAGCAAUGGGUCUCACCAUAGCUGCUGGAAUCACACCUGAGAACUGAGAUAUACCAAUAUUUAACAUUGUUACAAAGAAGAAAAGAUACAGAUUUGGUGAAUUUGUUACUGUGAGGUACAGUCAGUACACAGCUGACUUAUGUAGAUUUAAGCUGCUAAUAUGCUACUUAACCAUCUAUUAAUGCACCAUUAAAGGCUUAGCAUUUAAGUAGCAACAUUGCGGUUUUCAGACACAUGGUGAGGUCCAUGGCUCUUGUCAUCAGGAUAAGCCUGCACACCUAGAGUGUCGGUGAGCUGACCUCACGAUGCUGUCCUCGUGCGAUUGCCCUCUCCUGCUGCUGGACUUCUGCCUUUGUUGGCCUGAUGUGCUGCUGUGAUGCUGGUCCUUCAUCUUAGGUGUUCAUGCAGUUCUAACACAGUUGGGGUUGGGUCAAUAGUUUCCCAAUUUCAGGAUAUUUCGAUGUCAGAAAUAACGCAUCUUAGGAAUGACUAAACAAGAUAAUGGCAGUUUAGGCUGCACAACUGGUAAAAUGACUGUAGAUAAAUGUUGUAAUUAGUGUACACGUUUGUAUUUUUGUUAAUAUAGCCGCUGCCAUAGUUUUCUAACUUGAACAGCCAUGAAUGUUUCAUGUCUCCCUUUUUUUUUGUCUAUAGCUGUUACCUAUUUUAGUGGUUGAAAUGAGAGCUAGUGAUGACAGAAGGAUGUGGAAUGUCUUCUUGACAUCAUUGUGUAUUGCUGGUAAUCAAGUUGGUAACGACUACUUCUAGCAGCUCUUACCACUAUGACUUAAGUGGUCCUGGAAGGCAGUAAGUGGAGGUUUGCAGCAUUCCUGCCUUCAUGAGGGCUUCUACCACUGACCACUUUGCACGUACCUGGCUCCCAGAUUUACUUAGGUACCCCACGAGUUGUCCACAUAAGCAGCUUCAUCUUUACCUUGCCAGAGUUGACAAUUAUGGGAUACUCUAGUCUACUUAUACUUGUGUUCCCAUCUGUCUGCCAUCCUCUGAAGGCCGGGACCCAGUCAUACAUCCUUAGAAACCAAAGUAUGGUUUUUGUUUUCUCUUGGAAUGUCAGGUCUUAAGGCAUUUAAUUGAGGGACAAAAAAAAAAAAAGCCGAUAUAGUAGCUAGCUACUUAAGCAUCCAUGGGUAUUGCUCCAUAUCAAAGCAGAUUUGCAGGACAGAGAGAGUAAAUUAGCCUUCAGUCUUGGUUUACAGCUUCCAAGGAGAGCCUUGGCCACCUGAAAUGUUAACUCGGUCCCUUCCUGUCUCUAGUUCAUCAGCACCUGCAGAUGCCUGACUCUUGUUAGCCUUACUAUUCAAUACAGUCCUUAGAUUCACGGUAUGCCUCUUCCUAUCCAGGCACCUAUUCUGAAUCACCAUGUUGCUCUGCAGCUAGAGUUGAUAGGAGAAAAUCCAUUUGGGUAGAUGGCCUAUGAAUUUGUAGUAGACUUUCAAAAUGAGUGAUUUGUUAGCUUGGUACUUUUAAGUUUGUGGUACAGAUCCUCCAAACCCAUACUCUGAGCAAUUAACUGCCUUGAACAUAGAGAAAAAUUAAGGCCUCACAGGAUGAGUCUCCAUUCUCUGUAAAUGCUUAUUUUAUCAUAGUCUUUAGCCUCUACUAUGAGUAAAAUGUUCUCUUCGGCCGGGUGUGGUGACUCACACCUGUAACCUCAGCACUUUGGGAGGCAGAGGUGGGAGGAUCACUUAGGUCCAGGAGUUCGAGACUAGCCUGGGCAACAUAGUGAGACACCGGAUCUACAAAAAAAUAAAAAGCCAGACUGGUGGUAUGUAUCUGUGUCCCAGCUAAUUGGGAGGGUGAGUUGGGAGGAUUGUUUGAGCCUAGGAGAGGGAGGUUGCAGUGAGCCGUGAUUGCACCACUGCACUCCAGCCUGGGCAACAGAGCAAGACCCUGUCUUGGAGAAACCAGAAUUUUGGAAGAGCAAAUGGGGCUGAGUGCAGUGGCUCAUGCCUGUAAUCCCAGCACUUAGGGUGCCAAUGUGGAUUACCUGAGCCCAGGAGUUUGAGACCAGCCUGGGUAACAGUGAGACCCCCCUCCCUACAAAAGAUUUUAAUAAUUAGUUGGGCGUAGUGGUGCAUGCCUGUAAUCCCAGCUACUCUGGAGACAGGUGGAGGGGAUUGCUUGAGCCUGGGAAGCUGAGGCUGCAGUAGCCAUGACUGCACCACUGCAUUCCAGCCUGGUUGACAGAGUGACCCUUGUCUCCAAGAAAAAAAAAAAGCAAAUGGGAUUAAGGACUCAUGGAAUGGGAAGGGGAAGGGGAGUCUUACUAUAUGUGGAAUAAACUUGCUCAGUGUUGCCACAGAGUUACAUUACCAAUGUGUAGAAGUCAGAAACUAGACUUCUAGUUUGGUUCAACAUUUGAGGGUUGUUUUAUAGCCAUCAAAGUAUUCAAGAGGUUGGAUGGCACUCAAAAGAUUCUACAUGUCUAGAAUCAAACUCAAAUCUGGCACGUAGGUGCUUCUUAGUAAAUGCUUAAUGAAUGCCACCAACUCUGCAAAGUAUUCAUUGAUUUUGAGACCUUAGUCAUGUUGCUACUAAAAGUAGGGCAUAUGACCGCCUAAGAAACAGAACUUCGAGAAGUCCUAACGUAACCACAGUAAAGCAGACUCCCCUUUCAGCAACCUCAAAGCAAAAAAAAAAAAAAAAAAACCAGUUAGCUGCUAUAUAAACACUAUACCAAGCACUAGGCUUAGAGGAAAAGAUGUCAGAUUGUACUGUCACUGGCUAUGUACCCAUAUUCUCUAAGACAGGGUAGCAUUUGUCUUUCAAACUGCAGGGUUUGAAAUCAGUUUUUGUGGGUGAUUGCAAUUUUUUAAUGAAAUGCAUUAGAACAUCUAAGCACGUCACCUACAGUUUUGUGAUGGUGCAUUUUUGCAUUGCAGUAUAGAUCUGUGCAUAGAUAUAUGCAUUAAGUGUAGCAAAUCGUGAUGUAAAUUUUUUACUGCUGGUCAUGGUCAAAAAGUAAGAUACGCUAGGAAAUUGAGUCACUAGGAGCAUGGAUGUAUAAGGCAGGUUUUAUACAACCAUUUAGAUUCAACAUUAAUGGUAGAGUGGCAUUUUACCAAAAAAAUGGGUGUAUUUGAUUUGGGUGCUGUAAGGCAAUUUGCUAGGACAUGGGAUAAUCAGAUUACACAAAAUCUAGGCAGUGAACAAGUCUUCAUCCUGGCCCAGGAAAUAGCCUAUUAAAAAAUGCUGUCCAGGCCAGGCACAGUGGCUCACACCUGUAAUCCCAGGACUUCGGGAGGCUGAGGCUGGAGGAUUGCUUGAGUUCAAGACCAGCCUGAGCAACACAGUGAAAACCCAUCUCAAAAAAAAAAAAAAAAAACCAAAAAAACUGUCCAGCUGUGGACUUUCAGGAUUCAGGACUGCUGGGGAUCAAGCCCAAGGAUGUUUUUCAGAGCUCUGUGAUUUAAGAUGCUCGAAAAGAGUGUCCAAGAGGAGUAAAGGUCAUGACAGAAUUUACUCCCAGGACAAUCUAAGUUCUGCCACAAGUACCCGUGGUGUCUGUUCCCACAACAAUGGCCCUUUCACAAGCUCUUGCCUCACAACCCCUGCAGAAGUCCUUCAACAAAACUAAUAAUAGACUAGUGAAACCUACUCCUCACAUGGGUAAGAGUUGCAGUGGGCAGGUGACCCUCCUCCCUGCCCCCAUCCUUUGCUUCCUCAAGCUCCCUGCCAACCUCUGGAUACAUCAAUGGGAAGGAAACCAGGGAAGCAUAGACCUAUAGUACAACAGGGGUGUAGUGACCACUGGACCUGAUGAAGCGAAUCUGCCUGAAAUUUAAUACGCCUUUUUAUUUCCCUUCUGUGUUAAAUCAAAUGAUCUGUUCUGCACUGAGCCAAGCAAGUUACUUUUAAAACUGGUGGCACCACUCAUUUGGGACUUGGAGACUGCUUUUAUCCAGAACCUGUUAAGAGAACAGGGGAUUUAAAUACAAAGGAAUAUGAAGGUGGUGUGCCUUAAAGACAGUCUAAAAUUAGGUUUUAGUUUGUUACAUUAUUUUGAAAUAUUAAACAUGAAAAUGUUAAAUCAGGAUGUGUGAGUUUUAAGAUGUUGAACACUGUCCUACAUCAGUGAGGAGGGAGGCAAUAAAGUAAUUUCAGAGUAAAACAGAUUGAGGAUGAAACCAAGACAGAAGUGAUGAUUUGGCUUUUUAUGAUUUUUGCUGUGGAAAUGGCAGUCGUGUGACUUUUCACUUGCAGUUUAAAUGAAAGGGUGAAGAGAAGCCUACCUGCCCUAAUGGCUCAGGGCUAUAUCCACCUCCCGGAUAACCCUGGCCCUUGGGACUCCAUCAUCUCCUUGAAGUAGCACUGAGAAUCCAAGAAGAGGCUCCGCUGCUUUUUGCACAUGUUACUGAGUUACAUCUCAGGAAGAUUUUUAAGCACGAGGAAGGAAAAUACAGGCCUGGCCAAGCAGGGUCCCCUUUUCGGUAUCAUCUUUGUUCCUAAUAAGCAAUCAAGGGGGGUGGGUGUGUUGGCUGGUAAAGGAACUACUAAGAUUCAGAAGCUUGUAGUCUUCAUUAUUUUGUUUUACAGGUUAAAAUAAACCACUUGACUGGG